AGUUCCGCUUCCGGCAGCGCGAGAUAAAUCACGAGAGGAAGCUUAAAUCUGUCGUUUGAAUUUAGGACCACCUCGGUGAGUGGUCGUUCUGGUGUGCUGUGUCAUACCUACUGUUUUUUAAAGUGAGGCGUAACCCGACAGUAAUUUCAAAACCAUUCGCCUCGACCGGCCUAAGGAAGGGUUUAAUUGAGUCUGUGGGGAGAUUUUGCGCAAGCGCCUUUGAGAUAGGAGGGCCUUGGGCGUUGCGAUGUCCCGCGCUAGCUGAGCAGAAAGGGCGAGUGCUGUUUCGGGCCUGGGGAGGUGCCUACUGGGUGUAAUUGAGUUUUACCAAACGGUCAUUUUCCUGCUGAUUCUGAGUGUGGUUGGACCUUGCCCUUAAGAUUCCGUUAACGAGUCGCCCAAAGCUUAGGAAAUGCUCCCUCACAGCGUUUGAGACUAAGCACUUUUGGCCGGCGUUGAAGAAUUCUCCCCAUUACUUUGAUCAGUCAUUUAAUCAGAAAUUUUGCCCCAAAUUUAAAUACGUGGCGGGGAGAAACGUGAGGUCAAGAGGGAAUCCUGUCACGUAGUUUUAAAAGAAAAAUGUCCACUUUAUCUCAGUGUAGGUUUUUCUUAAAUGGGCAUUUCUGAACCAAAGUAGAUACUUUUUAAAGUGGAAAUGCAUUUAUCCCAUGUGGCUUCAUGUGAAUGCAUAUGGCGAUGAAGGCAUUUUUUUGUUCAAUGAAUUUGUACUCUGAAGUGAACCAGAUUACAGAGAAGUGUAUUUAAAUUUACAGGUCCUUGACGUUGCAUAAAAUUGUGCGUGUCCAUUUUUUGGAGCUUAAAAUAGAAUAAUUCAAAUGUCAGAAUUCCGAUCCAAGUUAACAUGUUGAUUGAAAAUUGCAGAUUUUAAGAUGGAACCAGCGGGUAUUAUAACCUUUUAGGGGCUUAAAUUGGUGGCUUUGUUUUUAACCCUUGGUGAAACAGUUAAGUCCUAAUCUUGACAUAAUACCUAACUGCCUUACUUUAUUGAACACAAAAUUAUUAAAGGAAUUAAGCAAUGAGUUGAUUUUAUUUGCUUUUAUGGAGGGGACAAAGUGUAUAAAGCUUAACCAAAUGUGACCCUGACAUUCCUCUUGCAAAACUACAAGUUGUAAUCAAUCACUUUCAUUUUUUCUUAUUCCUACAUGUUUAAGUACAUUAAGUAAUGAUUUUAAGAGAAAUUCUUGAAAAUAUGAGCAUAUCCAAAGAAGUCCCAGGACAGUCUUUCUUUAUGUAGUAGAAACCACUUAAUCCCCCUUGUAAAUGAUACCUUUACUUAGCAAUCAGAGUAUAAGAAGAUAUUUAUAUUUGUCUCGAAUAUUACAGUUUCAAGCCAUUUUCUCAUAUGUAUGGGCUUUGAAAAAAAAAAAACAACUUUCAUUUACGUUACUUUUGUAUAUGAAUACCAAUUAUUAGCAGUAAAACUUUUAACUACUUCAAAGGCUAUGCUUUUCGUGAACUGAGUUUUCUUUCUUACGCAUUUUCUAUUUCUCCUUGUCAUCUGUCUCUCUACCUCCAGAACCAGCAGUUUGUGAACUGCAUUAGACUGUUAUAUCGUUAUAAAAGGAUACAAUUCGUUCACAAUGGUCCGUAGUGGAAAAAAUGGUGACCUUCAUCUUAAACAGAUUGCAUAUUACAAACGAACUGGUGAAUAUCAUUCAACUACACUGCCAAGUGAGAGAAGUGGCAUAAGAAGAGCAGCAAAAAAAUUUGUCUUCAAAGAAAAAAAGCUGUUUUAUGUUGGAAAAGACAGAAAACAAAAUCGUUUGGUAAUUGUUUCAGAAGAGGAAAAAAAGAAAGUCUUAAGAGAAUGCCAUGAAAAUGACAGUGGAGCUCAUCAUGGUAUAUCCAGGACCCUCACUCUGGUAGAAUCCAAUUAUUAUUGGACAUCUGUGACCAAUGAUGUCAAACAGUGGGUAUAUGCUUGUCAGCAUUGCCAAGUGGCAAAAAAUACAGUUAUUGUAGCACCGAAACAGCACCUUCUCAAGGUGGAAAAUCCAUGGAGUUUAGUUACUGUUGAUCUGAUGGGGCCUUUUCAUACAAGCAACAGAAGUCAUGUAUAUGCUAUAAUCAUGACAGAUUUGUUCACCAAAUGGAUUGUGAUUUUGCCUCUAUGUGAUGUUUCAGCAUCAGAAGUUUCUAAAGCUAUUAUCAAUAUAUUUUUCUUAUAUGGACCUCCUCAGAAAAUAAUAAUGGACCAAAGAGAUGAAUUCAUUCAACAGAUCAAUAUUGAACUGUACAGAUUGUUUGGCAUAAAGCAAAUUGUAAUUUCUCACACCUCUGGAACUGUUAACCCAACGGAAAGUACACCUAACACAAUCAAAGCAUUUCUCUCCAAACACUGUGCUGACCACCCAAACAAUUGGGAUGAUCACCUAUCAGCUGUUUCAUUUGCCUUCAAUGUAACUCACUUGGAACCUACUAAAAAUACACCAUAUUUUCAAAUGUUUAGUCGAAAUCCUUAUAUGCCUGAGACUUCAGAUAGUCUUCAUGAAGUGGAUGGUGAUAAUACAAGUAUGUUUGCCAAAAUUCUAGAUGCAAUUAAAGAAGCUGAUAAAAUAAUGGAGAAUAAGACAACUUCACUGGGCCAGAUGGAGAACAACAAUUUGGAUGAACUAAAUAAAAGCAAGAUCAUUGUUAAAAAGAAACCCAAACAAUUAAAUCCAUUUCAUUUAAAAGUGGGUCAUGAAGUUUUAAGACAAAGGAAAAAUUGGUGGAAGGAUGGUCGUUUUCAGUCUGAAUGGGUUGGUCCUUGUGUCAUAGACUAUAUUACAGAAAGUGGAUGUGCUGUCCUGAGAGACAACACUGGGGUUAGACUGAAAAGACCUAUCAAAAUGUCCCACCUUAAGCCCUACAUAAGAGAAUCCAGUGAACAAGAAAGUCUUUAUCUCUUGCAAGGUUCAGUAGUGGCAGAUCAUGACUACAUUGGAUUGCCUGAAAUUCCGAUUGGAGCAUAUCAAGCAAAUAUUCUGGUGGAAGAUGCAACUAUUGGUAUAGUCGAUAAUGAAUUACUGACAUCAAGCAAGGAUCGUGAACUAUUAGAAUAUAGAAAUACGAAAAUCUCUCCAUUGAUAGACGAUCAUAGUUCUCUUGAAAAGCAGACUUUCAGUCUGUUGGACUCUUCAAACCAGGUUCUUGAAUACUUAAGUUAGUAAAUACCAAAAUUUAUUUAAAUUGUUUGUUUAGAAUAUAAAUUCUUAAUGAUAUCUUAUUCAUUAAAAACGUUGUAUAGAAGAAGUAUCUUGACACAUUCUUAAUGACUAUAUUCUGAAGGUUUAUUUUAUAGUUCUUAUCUAAAAUUAUGCCACAUUUGAAUAUCAGUAUACGUACAUAUGAAGGCAAAGGAAGCAUGUAAUAUAUAGAAUUCACUUUUUCUUCUAAAAAGAGAACAGGCAAAGCACCCCUACUUCUUGGGAAAUAAAUUCCAGCCCAAAUCUCUCAAACCUUUGUAUGGUUUUGGCACCGUUUCUAAGUUUUAAAUUUUCUGAAAUUCUCUACCAUUUAAACAGUAAGUUUGAACUACCUUGAAUGGAAUUGAUAAAUACUGAAUCAACUGUAACAAUGAAUGAAAUGAAGCUUCUUUCUGUUUCAUUAGAACUUCUAAAAACAAGAUUGUAUGAAAAAAUAUAGGGUUAUUUAAUAGGCUUUCACAGAAUAUUGGUAAUUUCAAAUUAUCUAAUUGGUUAGAUAGGGUCAGGAUUAGGGUCUGAAACUAUGUAUUGGUUGGGAAACAAUUUGUUUAUUUUCAUACUAUAUAUUAAAGAUAAAACCAUCGACCAGGCAUGGUGGCCCACACCUGUAAUCCCAGCGCUUUGGGAAGCCAAGGCAGGAUGAUCACUUGACCCCAGGAGUUCGAGACCAGCCUGGGCAACACAGGGAGACCCUAUCUCUACAGAAAAAUGUUUAAAAAUUAGCCAGGUGUGGUGGCACAUGCCUGCGGUCCCAGCUACUCAGGAGGCUGAAGUAGGAGCAUUGCUUGACCCCAGGAGGUCGAGGCUGCAGUGAGCCGCGCUCAUGCCACAGCUCUCCAGCCUGGGCGACAGGGCAAGACCUGUCUCAACAACAACAACAAAAGUAUCCGUUAAGAAUUUUUUCUGCAAUCAUAAAAUCAUAAAAUAACCAGUAUCAAAGAUUUUAAACUGUAAUUUCUAUGAUAUUCAUAAAUAUAAAAUAAAUAUUGUUCAAUAAAUAUUUAUUCUAAAGCACUAUGAAAAGAACUGUGGGAAAAGUAAAAGAUGAGUCAAACGUGUACCUCAUUCUUAUAAAGGACUUACUGUCUGGUAGGUAAUAAACUAUGUAAGCCAUGUACAGCACAAGUUAAGGCAUGCUAAAUUGCAGAAGACAGGUGUAGAUAAUGUACUUAGGGAGGCAAAAAGAGAGAAGUUGUUUUUACAUAGGAAAUUUGUGUUUAUCCUUAUGGAAGAAGGAUCAUUUAAGCUUGACCUUGAAGAAUGUAUAGGAUUUGGUAAAUGGAUACAAAAGAAUUAGGGGAGAAGUAAUACACAGAAAUGGAAAAGUAUUGUAAUGAUUCAUAAAAAGGCAGGGCUUCUUGUUGUCUACACUGCCUCGGGUAUAAAGUGAAGAAGCAAGAUAAUGAGGGAUAAAGCUGAAAAGGUAAGUAGGAAACCUUAUGGAGAGCUUUGAAUACUAUUAAGGAUUGAUAUGUGCCCCUCCCAAAAUUUGUGUUGAAGUCUUAACCCCCACCACCUCAAAAUGUGACCUUAUUUGGAAAUGAGGUUGUUGCAAGUGUAAUUAGUUGAGAUCAUAUUUCAAUAGGGUGGGCUCUAAUACAGUAUUACUGGUGUUCUGAUAAAAGGGGAAAAUUUGAACACAGACUCAAGGAGAAUGCCAUGUGAAGAUAAAGGCAGAGUUUAAGAUUAUGUUUCUAUAUGCCAAGAAAUGACAGAGAUUGCCAGAAAACUACCAGAAGUUAGGGGAGAGGCAUUGAAUACAUUUUUCCUCAUUCCUCAGAAGACCAACCCUGUCAAUACCUUAUCUCAGACUUUUGCCUCCAGAACUGUGAGACAAUAAAAUUCUAUUGUUUCAGCCA